AGUAGUUCCGCUUCCUGUCCGACUGUGGUGUCUUUGCUGAGGGUCACAUUGAGCUGCAGGUUGAAUCCGGGGUGCCUUUAGGAUUCAGCACCAUGGCGGAAGACAUGGAGACCAAAAUCAAGAACUACAAGACCGCCCCUUUUGACAGCCGCUUCCCCAACCAGAACCAGACUAGAAACUGCUGGCAGAACUACCUGGACUUCCACCGCUGUCAGAAGGCAAUGACCGCUAAAGGAGGCGAUAUCUCUGUGUGCGAAUGGUACCAGCGUGUGUACCAGUCCCUCUGCCCCACAUCCUGGGUCACAGACUGGGAUGAGCAACGGGCUGAAGGCACGUUUCCCGGGAAGAUCUGAACUGGCUGCAUCUCCCUUUCCUCUGUCCUCCAUCCUUCUCCCAGGAUGGUGAAGGGGGACCUGGUACCCAGUGAUCCCCACCCCAGGAUCCUAAAUCAUGACUUACCUGCUAAUAAAAACUCAUUGGAAAAGUGA